GCGCGCCCGCGGCGCUCCAUCCCAAACACACACACAUUUUUCCCCCGGACUUGGAAAGUCACCCAAAGCCGCCCCAAGUGCAGGUACAACAACUGCGUAGCCAUUGGCUAAUAAUUGUGCGAAGGGUGCGUUGGUUGCAGAGUCAGGCAUGGUAUGCGCCGUGGCAAUGCCAUCUGCUGAUUGGCUGGCAGGAACGAGAAUCUCUUACCUGGCUGGCUGGUUAUCACACAAGGCAAACAGACCUUGCUGACUGAAGGCAAAGACUCCUCCAUCCCACCUGCCCUCCCAGCUGCCACGGCCAUCGACCCCUCCUUUACAAGGGGCUCCUGCAACUCCCCAGCAGCACGUGUUGGAAUGGACUUCGGACCCUGGCCUCUUGGGAUGCAAAGGAUGAAGUGACACCCCCAGCUACAUCCGAGGAGGUUCUAGGACCUGCUACGAGAGUUUGGGACCAAGGAGAAGAGAAUGGAUCUUGGAACAGCUGAGGGCACCCGGUGCACGGACCCGCCUGCAGGCAAGCCCGCCAUGGCGCCCAAACGCAAGGGUGGCCUGAAGCUGAACGCCAUCUGCGCCAAGCUGAGCCGCCAGGUGGUGGUGGAGAAGCGAGCUGACGCCGGCUCCCACACGGAGGGCAGCCCAUCGCAGCCCCGGGACCAAGAGCGCAGUGGCCCUGAGUCUGGGGCAGCCCGGGCCCCCCGCAGCGAGGAAGACAAGAGACGGGCAGUGAUCGAGAAGUGGGUGAACGGGGAGUACAGCGAGGAGCCGGCACCCACACCCGUGUUGGGGCGGAUUGCCCGCGAGGGCCUGGAGCUGCCUCCCGAGGGUGUCUACAUGGUGCAGCCCCAGGGGUGCAGCGAUGAGGAAGACCACGCGGAGGAGCCCUCCAAGGACGGCGGUGCCCUGGAGGAGAAGGAUUCGGACGGGGCAGCCUCCAAGGAGGACAGCGGCCCCAGCACCAGGCAGGCUUCAGGAGAGGCCUCCUCGCUGCGGGACUACGCGGCCUCCACCAUGACCGAGUUCCUCGGCAUGUUUGGCUAUGAUGACCAGAACACGCGGGACGAGCUGGCCAGGAAGAUCAGCUUUGAGAAGCUGCACGCGGGCUCCACCCCGGAGGCAGCCACCUCCUCCAUGCUGCCCACCUCCGAGGAUACCCUCAGCAAGCGGGCGCGGUUCUCUAAGUAUGAGGAGUACAUCCGCAAGCUCAAGGCUGGCGAGCAGCUCUCCUGGCCGGCCCCCAGCACCAAGACCGAGGAGCGGGUGGGCAAGGAGGUGGUGGGCACCCUGCCCGGCCUGCGGCUGCCCAGCAGCACGGCCCACCUGGAGACCAAGGCCACCAUCCUGCCCCUGCCGUCGCACAGCAGUGUCCAGAUGCAGAACCUGGUAGCCCGGGCCUCCAAGUACGACUUCUUCAUCCAAAAACUGAAGACCGGCGAGAAUCUGCGGCCCCAGAACGGGAGCACCUACAAGAAGCCAUCCAAGUACGACCUGGAGAAUGUCAAGUACCUGCACCUCUUCAAACCCGGGGAGGGCAGCCCCGACAUGGGCGGGGCCAUCGCCUUCAAGACAGGCAAGGUGGGGCGCCCUUCCAAGUACGACGUCCGGGGCAUCCAGAAGCCAGGCCCCGCCAAGGUUCCGCCCACCCCCAGCCUGGCUCCCGCACCCCUCGCCAGCGUGCCCAGUGCCCCCAGCGCCCCCGGGCCAGGGCCAGAGCCUCCUGCCUCCCUGUCCUUCAACACUCCCGAGUACCUGAAGUCAACCUUCUCCAAAACAGACUCCAUCACCACGGGGACCGUCUCCACUGUCAAGAACGGACUGCCCACAGAUAAACCAGCCGUCACUGAAGAUGUAAACAUUUACCAGAAAUAUAUUGCCAGGUUCUCGGGCAGCCAGCACUGUGGCCACAUCCACUGUGCCUACCAGUACCGCGAGCACUACCACUGCCUUGACCCUGAGUGUAACUACCAGAGGUUCACGAGUAAGCAGGACGUGAUCCGCCACUACAACAUGCACAAGAAGCGCGACAACUCCCUGCAGCACGGCUUCAUGCGUUUCAGCCCGCUGGACGACUGCAGCGUCUACUACCACGGCUGCCACCUCAAUGGGAAGAGCACCCACUAUCACUGCAUGCAGGUGGGCUGUAACAAGGUGUACACGAGCACGUCUGACGUGAUGACCCACGAGAACUUCCACAAGAAGAAUACCCAGCUCAUUAACGACGGCUUCCAGCGCUUCCGAGCCACCGAAGACUGUGGCACAGCCGACUGCCAGUUCUACGGACAGAAGACCACGCACUUCCACUGCAGGCGCCCCGGCUGCACAUUCACUUUCAAGAACAAGUGUGACAUCGAGAAGCACAAGAGCUACCACAUCAAGGACGAUGCCUACGCCAAGGACGGCUUCAAGAAGUUCUACAAGUACGAGGAGUGCAAGUACGAGGGCUGCGUGUACAGCAAGGCUACCAACCACUUCCACUGCAUCCGCGCCGGCUGCGGCUUCACCUUCACCUCCACCAGCCAGAUGACCUCUCACAAGCGCAAGCAUGAGCGCCGGCACAUCCGCUCCUCGGGCGCGCUGGGGCUGCCGCCCUCGCUGCUGGGCGCCAAGGACACGGAGCACGAGGAGUCCAGCAACGACGACCUUGUUGACUUCUCCGCCCUGAGCAGCAAGAACUCCAGCCUGAGCGCCUCCCCUACCAGCCAGCAGUCCUCUGCGUCCCUGGCUGCCGCCACUGCCGCCACCGAGGCUGGGCCCAGUGCCACCAAACCUCCCAACAGCAAGAUCUCGGGGCUGCUGCCCCAGGGCCUGCCUGGCUCAAUCCCCCUGGCCCUGGCCCUCUCCAACUCGGGCCUGCCCACCCCCACGCCCUACUUCCCCAUACUGGCUGGCCGUGGGAGCACCUCCCUGCCUGUGGGCACCCCCAGCCUCCUGGGUGCCGUGUCGUCUGGGUCAGCAGCCUCAGCCACCCCUGACACACCCACGCUGGUCGCCUCGGGAGCUGGAGACUCAGCCCCCGUGGCUGCCGCCUCUGUCCCGGCACCACCCGCCUCCAUCAUGGAGAGGAUCUCUGCAAGCAAGGGCCUCAUCUCGCCCAUGAUGGCCAGGCUGGCUGCAGCUGCCCUCAAGCCCUCUGCCACCUUUGACCCAGGAAGCGGGCAGCAGGUCACCCCAGCCAGGUUCCCCCCGGCCCAAGUGAAGCCGGAACCCGGUGAGAGCACCGGCGCCCCAGGCCCCCACGAAGCCUCCCAGGACCGCAGUCUAGACCUGACUGUGAAGGAGCCCAGCAACGAAUCAAAUGGCCACGCAGUCCCGGCAAAUUCAUCUCUUUUAUCCUCGCUUAUGAAUAAGAUGUCUCAGGGCAACCCUGGCCUGGGCAGCCUGCUGAACAUCAAGGCGGAAGCGGAGGGGAGCCCCGCUGCGGAGCCCUCGCCCUUCCUAGGCAAGGCCGUGAAGGCGCUGGUUCAGGAGAAGUUGGCAGAGCCCUGGAAGGUGUACCUGCGCAGGUUUGGUACAAAGGACUUCUGUGACGGCCAGUGUGACUUCCUCCACAAGGCCCACUUCCACUGCGUGGUGGAGGAAUGCGGCGCGCUCUUCAGCACCUUGGACGGGGCCAUCAAGCACGCAAACUUCCACUUCCGGACAGAGGGAGGAGCAGCAAAAGGAAACACAGAGGCUGCCUUUCCGGCCUCGGCCGCCGAGACCAAACCUCCCAUGGCCCCCUCGUCCCCUCCGGUCCCUCCUGUCACCACGGCCACGGUGUCCUCUCUGGAGGGGCCCGCUCCCAGCCCGGCCUCCGUGCCCUCCACCCCCACCCUGCUCGCCUGGAAGCAGCUGGCUUCCACCAUACCCCAGAUGCCUCAGAUCCCAGCGUCAGUGCCUCACCUGCCCGCCUCGCCCUUGGCAACGACUUCUCUAGAGAACGCCAAGCCCCAGGUCAAACCCGGAUUCCUCCAGUUCCAGGAGAACGAUCCUUGCCUCGCCACGGACUGCAAGUACGCCAACAAGUUCCACUUCCACUGUCUCUUUGGGAACUGCAAGUACGUCUGCAAAACGUCUGGCAAGGCCGAAUCCCACUGCCUGGACCACAUCAACCCCAACAACAACCUGGUGAACGUGCGAGACCAGUUUGCAUACUACUCUCUGCAGUGUCUCUGUCCCAACCAGCACUGCGAGUUCCGAAUGCGUGGGCACUACCACUGCCUCCGCACCGGCUGCUAUUUUGUGACCAACAUCACCACCAAGCUCCCCUGGCACAUCAAGAAGCAUGAGAAGGCGGAGCGGCGGGCAGCCAAUGGCUUCAAAUACUUCACCAAGCGCGAGGAGUGUGGCAGGCUAGGUUGCAAGUACAACCAGGUGAACAGCCACUUCCACUGCAUCCGGGAGGGCUGCCAGUUCUCCUUCCUCCUCAAGCACCAGAUGACCUCCCACGCGCGGAAGCACAUGCGGAGGAUGCUGGGGAAGAACUUCGACCGCGUGCCCCCCUCCCAGGGCCCCCCAGGCCUGAUGGAUGCUGAGACAGAUGAGUGCAUGGACUACACUGGCUGCAGCCCAGGCGCCAUGUCCUCUGAGUCAUCCACCAUGGACCGGAGCUGCUCCAGCACCCCCGUGGGUAACGAGAGCACCGCGGCAGGCUGCCCGGCUCCUCCUCCUCCUCCUCUUCCUCCUCCUGCGGCCGCUGGUGAUGAGGCUGCCCGCACGGCCCCGCAGCCGCCAGCGACUCCAUCCUUCUCGCCGGCCACGCUCCGGCCGCCCCUCCCCCCCCUCCCCUGCCUCUUCUCUCCGUCCUGUCUCUCAUACUCUCUGCUCAGUGCCACUCUCGGAGCCGGCCGGGGCCUGGCCCAUCCCACCUGCAGCCCGCCCAGCUUCCCGCCCGUCACUGCCACUCCAACUCCAGUAAAAAGUGACGUCCCCCUAGUUCAGGAUGCUGCAGGGAACACCAUCUCUAUGCCGACAGCCUCGGGGGCCAAAAAGCGCUUCUGGAUCAUCGAGGACAUGUCGCCCUUCGGCAAGCGGCGGAAGACGGCGUCCUCCCGGAAGAUGCUGGACGAGGGCAUGAUGCUGGAGGGCUUCCGGCGCUUCGACCUUUACGAGGACUGCAAGGACGCAGCUUGUCAGUUCUCGCUCAAGGUCACCCACUACCACUGCACGCGCGAGAACUGCGGCUACAAGUUCUGCGGGCGCACGCACAUGUACAAGCACGCGCAGCACCACGACCGCGUGGACAACCUGGUGCUGGACGACUUCAAGCGCUUCAAGGCCUCACUCAGCUGCCACUUCGCCGACUGCCCCUUCUCGGGCACCAGCACGCACUUCCACUGCCUGCGCUGCCGCUUCCGCUGCACCGACAGCACCAAGGUCACGGCGCAUCGCAAGCACCACGGCAAACAGGACGUGAUCAGCGCCGCGGGCUUCUGCCAGUUCAGCUCCAGCGCCGACUGCGCCGUGCCCGACUGCAAGUACAAGCUCAAGUGCUCGCACUUCCACUGCACCUUCCCGGGCUGCCGCCACACGGUGGUGGGCAUGUCGCAGAUGGACUCGCACAAGCGCAAGCACGAGAAGCAGGAGCGCGGCGAGCCCGCGGCAGAGGGCCCCGCGCCCGGGCCUCCCAUCAGUCUGGACGGCUCCCUGUCGCUGGGCGCCGAGCCGGGCUCGCUGCUCUUCCUGCAGUCGGCGGCCGCCGGCCUGGGCCUGGCGCUGGGCGACGCGGGCGACCCCGGCCCGCCCGACGCCGCCGCCCCCGGGCCGCGCGAGGGCGCCGCCGCCGCCGCCGCCGCAGCUGGGGAGUCCUCGCAGGAGGACGAGGAGGAGGAGCUGGAGCUGCCGGAGGAGGAGGCCGAAGACGACGAGGACGAGGACGACGACGAGGACGACGACGACGAGGACGACGACGAGGACGACGACGACGAGGACCUGCGCACCGACUCGGAGGAGUCGCUGCCCGAGGCGGCGGCGGAGGCGGCGGGCGCGGGCGCGCGGACCCCGGCCUUGGCGGCGCUGGCGGCCCUGGGCGCCCCCGGCCCCGCGCCCACUGCAGCCUCCUCGCCCUAGCGGCGCCCGCGGGUGGCCCUGGCGGCGGCCUCGGCCUCGGCCUCGGGAGCGGCGCCGCCCCGCGCGAAGCGGCCCCUGGGCAGAGCCCCGCGCCCCGCCGGUGCUUCCGGACCCCGAGUCCGUCUCAGGACAGAGGCGGGGACCCCUCUGGUGCUCCGCGGCCGAGGACACAGGCGGCGGCGGUGGCCCUGCUCUAGGGAGGCCGGGUCUCUUCAGGGAAACAGAAGGUGCUCUUGUCCCGGGGUAGGGAACCUAGGAGCAGGGGUCCCGGGCGAAUGCGGCGCAGCUCCCGGCCGCUGCCCCGGCGCCCCUCCCCGCGGCCGAUUCGGCCCCGCGACCAUUGCUCAGGACUGGGACGGGCGCUGGGGGCCACCGGGACCCCCACCGCGCGCCACCAGGGCGGGGUGGCUCCUGGAGCCGCUGGCGGGGCCUCCCUCAUGCAGCUAGGAUCCUCCCCCCUGCCCAGGGGGAGACGGGCAGAAGGCAGUCAGCACGGGUGACACUACAGGGACCGUGGAGGAAGCCUCACGGGAGUAGCAGCCGCGGAGCUCCAGCUCAGCCCCACCCCAGGGCCCGGCUGCUCCCCCAGGCCUGGGUCGGGUCUGUUUGGCGACUCCCUGGCCCCAGCCUCCGCCCCAGGGAAACCGAGGCUGCGUCCAAAACCCAGAGUAGCCCGCUGGGGGCCGGGGCGGGGUCUCGGCCACCCUGGUGGUGCAAACAGGAAGGAUGCGCCUGGUUUUGGCUUUAAUGUUCAAAAUGGAAAAAAAUACAAGAAAGUUGUACAGUAUUUUUCCUGUAAAGGUUAUUAUUCUACAUAGAACAAAAAGGAAGAAAGCAGGCGUGGUGAGAGUGCAGACCCGCCUGGGCCCGGCCUGAGGUUGGAGGCUCAGUCCCGUUUAUCCUGUGGGAUUUGGUCCAGGGUUUUUGUAGAGGCCUUAACUGUUUGAGGCUGUCUGUCUUCACAAUAGCACUGAUGGGAGCUGCGUGAUUCCAACUCUUAACUUGAAUUUUGUAGAGACAAGAAAAAAGGACUAUUACUGUUGAUCCAAGUUUGUAGUUAAUUUAACAUUUGAGUUCUCUCUUGGUGAUGCGUGUGGCUUUAUAGGGCUUUUUUUUUUUUCCAGUUUGUUUUAUUACUUUGUUUGGGAUGCUUCUUCGCUGGUGCAGUCUACCCAGAUUGGGUUCCCUUUGCAAAACAUCCCCCUUCCUGGAGAUGAUGAUGCCAUCGAAGCCCGGGCCAGGGCCUGACCUGGCAGGCACACACCUGGCCAGUGGCUCUGAGGUCCCCGGGGACCGAGUCCCCUGCGAGGGCAGGCUGCCCGAGGCCACACCUGCCCACCUUCCCUACUCCAGGCCACCAGCUGGUGUCAGAUUGGGCCACCGGGAGAGAACAGGCCUAGGAGGGAAUGGAAGGCUGGCGGGGAGGCUGUCAUCCAGAAGCCUCCUCCCCAGAGGUCUCCAGGAGGAACCUGGCUCAACUGGGGGGCAGUGGUUUACUUUUCCCUUUUUUCUUCCUUUCUUUUGUCCUCUCAGCUGCCCACAGCCAGAAAGCCAGGACCACCCGAACUGGACAGGGAGCAGGGAGGGAGGAGUGGUCGCACGGAGCGUACCUGAUUCAACAGGAAAUCAGUUAUUUUCUAAAACAGCCCCUACCAGAGCCUCCUGAACUCUGUGGGCACCACGUGCUGCUGUGAGCAUCUGCCCAGACAGUGACCCGCCACAGGCCCCGGGCGUCUGUGGAAGGAGUUUUGUAAAGGAAAAAAAAACACACACACACAAACAUUUUUUCAAUGUAGCAAAAUCAAACUUAAAAAAAAAAAAGAAGAAAAGAAGAAGAUGCCGACAGUGCGGAGUCUAGCCUUUUGUAAACUUCAUAUUGCACACUAGGACUAUAAGCCAUUGCUAGCUCAUUUUGAAUUUUAACGUGUAAUUUUUGUUUUAUUUUCUUUCUGUGGGGAAACAAUGCUUGAUCCACCAAUGCUCUUUUUAAUGUUUUAUAACUAUGUAUGUGUAUAUAUAUAAAUAUCAAAUAAUAUGUAUGCACAUAUGUGUGUGUAUAUAUCUAUAUGUAUAUACAUAUAUAGAUAUAUAGAGAUAUAUAGAGAGGUUUUGAGACAAAAAAAAUACAGAACGUGAAACCCGAGCUGAACAGCGUGUGCUCUGAUUACUUGAAUCUGGUCUCCUCGGCACCUGGUUAUUAAGAACUGAAUAUUUUUCCACUUGAAUUUAGUGCUAUUAGAAAUUUAAUAUAUGUGUUUUAUUUAUUUGAUUUUUUUUUUUUUUUUUGCAUGACUGAUGCAAGGUUUGACAUUUUCACUCAAUAAAAACUGGAAAAAAA